GCCUGUCUGCUCCGGCACCACCAUGUCGCUCAUGGUCAUCAGCAUGGCAUGUGUUGGGUUCUUCUGGCUGCAGGGGGCCUGGCCACAUGAGGGUGGUCAGGACAAGCCCUUGCUUUCUACCUGGCCCAGCCUUGUGGUGCCUCCAGAACAUGUGACUCUUCGGUGUCACUCUAAUCUUGGGUUUAACAACUUCAGUCUGUACAAGGAUGAUGGGGUGCCUGUCCCUGAACACUACAACAGAAUAUUCUGGAAAAGCCUUUUCAUGGGCCCUGUGACCCCGUCACACACAGGGACCUAUAGAUGCCGGGGUUCACACCCACACUCCCCCAGUGGGUGGUCGGCACCCAGCAACCCCCUGCUGAUCAUGGUCACAGGAUUCCGCAGAAAACCUUCCCUCCUGGCCCACCCAGGUCGCCUGGUGAAAUCAGAAGAGACAGUCAUCCUGCAAUGUUGGUCAGAUGUCAUGUUUGAGCACUUCCUUCUGCACAGAGAGGGGACGUUUAACGACACUUUGCGCCUCAUUGGAGAGCACAUUGAUGGGGUCUCCAAGGCCAACUUCUCCAUCGGUCGCAUGAGGCAAGACCUGGCAGGGACCUACAGAUGCUACGGUUCUGUUCCUCACUCCCCCUAUCAGUUUUCAGCUCCCAGUGACCCUCUGGACAUCGUGAUCACAGGUCUAUAUGAGAAACCUUCUCUCUCAGCCCAGCCGGGCCCCACGGUUCUGGCAGGAGAGAGCGUGACCUUGUCCUGCAGCUCCUGGAGCUCCUAUGACAUGUACCAUCUAUCCACGGAGGGGGAGGCCCAUGAACGUAGGUUCUCUGCAGGGCCCAAGGUCAACGGAACAUUCCAGGCCGACUUUCCUCUGGGCCCUGCCACCCAAGGAGGAACCUACAGAUGCUUCGGCUCUUUCCAUGACUCUCCCUACGAGUGGUCAAAGUCAAGUGACCCACUGCUUGUUUCUGUCACAGGAAACCCUUCAAAUAGUUGGCCUUCACCCACUGAACCAAGCUCCAAAACCGGUAACCCCAGACACCUACACGUUCUGAUUGGGACCUCAGUGGUCAAACUCCCUUUCACCAUCCUCCUCUUCUUUCUCCUUCAUCGCUGGUGCUCCAACAAAAAAAAUGCAUCUGUAAUGGACCAAGGGCCUGCGGGGAACAGAACAGUGAACAGGGAGGAUUCUGAUGAACAGGACCAUCAGGAGGUGUCAUACGCAUAAUUGGAUCACUGUGUUUUCACACAGAGAAAAAUCACUCCCCCUUCUCAGAG